GAAACGUGAAGAAGGUGAAGAUGGCGGUGGCCAGGGCCGGGGUCUUGGGAGUCCAGUGGCUGCAAAGGGCAUCCCGGAACGUGAUGCCGCUGGGCGCACGGACAGCCUCCCACAUGACCAAGGACAUGUUCCCGGGGCCCUAUCCUAGGACCCCAGAAGAACGGGCCGCCGCCGCCAAGAAGUAUAAUAUGCGUGUGGAAGACUACGAACCUUACCCGGAUGAUGGCAUGGGGUAUGGCGACUACCCGAAGCUCCCUGACCGCUCACAGCAUGAGAGAGAUCCAUGGUAUAGCUGGGACCAGCCGGGCCUGAGGUUGAACUGGGGUGAACCGAUGCACUGGCACCUAGACAUGUACAACAGGAACCGUGUGGAUACAUCCCCCACACCUGUUUCUUGGCAUGUCAUGUGUAUGCAGCUCUUCGGUUUCCUGGCUUUCAUGAUAUUCAUGUGCUGGGUGGGGGACGUGUACCCUGUCUACCAGCCUGUGUGUAGGCACCACUUCUCUUACAAUUUAGGCUUUCUCUCUGCCUUGGGCUGAGUGAGGAAGAGGAGUGCUGUUCCUGCCUUCCUAGCCCAGCUGGGUCUGACCAGAGGCUACUGUGUACCCAUUUACCAUGCGUGAUUGUUAACUCAGAGUGGGGUGUAGCCAGGUAUUGACUGAAUGUAUGUUCUUGCUGACCUGUGUUUUUUUCUGUAGGGACCAAAGCAGUAUCCUUACAAUAAUCUGUACCUGGAACGAGGCGGUGAUCCCUCCAAAGAACCAGAGCGGGUGGUUCACUAUGAGAUCUGAGGAGGCUUCGUGGGCUUUUGGGUCCUCUAACUAGGACUCCCUCAUUCCUAGAAAUUUAACCUUAAUGAAAUCCCUAAUAAAACUCAGUGCUGUGUUA